CAGCACAGCUAACUUUGGAGACCUACCAAGAAUGGUGCAAUGAUUCAGCAGCUACUCAUGACCCUCUUUCCCAGCUGCCCGCUCCUCAGCACCCGAAGAUUCGCCUGUACAACGCAGAGCAGGUCCUGAGUUGGGAGCCAGUGGCCCUGAGCAAUAGCACGAGGCCUGUUGUCUACCAAGUGCAGUUUAAAUACACCGACAGUAAAUGGUUCACGGCCGACAUCAUGUCCAUAGGGGUGAAUUGUACACAGAUCACAGCAACAGAGUGUGACUUCACUGCCGCCAGUCCCUCAGCAGGCUUCCCAAUGGAUUUCAAUGUCACUCUACGCCUUCGAGCUGAGCUGGGAGCACUCCAUUCUGCCUGGGUGACAAUGCCUUGGUUUCAACACUAUCGGAAUGUGACUGUCGGGCCUCCAGAAAACAUUGAGGUGACCCCAGGAGAAGGCUCCCUCAUCAUCAGGUUCUCCUCUCCCUUUGACAUCGCUGAUACCUCCACGGCCUUUUUUUGUUAUUAUGUCCAUUACUGGGAAAAAGGAGGAAUCCAACAGGUCAAAGGCCCUUUCAGAAGCAACUCCAUUUCAUUGGAUAACUUAAAACCCUCCAGAGUGUACUGUUUACAAGUCCAGGCACAACUGCUUUGGAACAAAAGUAACAUCUUUAGAGUCGGGCAUUUAAGCAACAUAUCUUGCUACGAAACAAUGGCAGAUGCCUCCACUGAGCUUCAGCAAGUCAUCCUGAUCUCCGUGGGAACAUUUUCGUUGCUGUCGGUGCUGGCAGGAGCCUGUUUCUUCCUGGUCCUGAAAUAUAGAGGCCUGAUUAAAUACUGGUUUCACACUCCACCAAGCAUCCCAUUACAGAUAGAAGAGUAUUUAAAAGACCCAACUCAGCCCAUCUUAGAGGCCUUGGACAAGGACAGCUCACCAAAGGAUGACGUCUGGGACUCUGUGUCCAUUAUCUCGUUUCCGGAAAAGGAGCAAGAAGAUGUUCUCCAAACGCUUUGAACCAAAGCAUGGGCCUAGCCCACUGGCUCCCUGGAAGAGAUCAAGCCAUCGGAGCUGCUAGAGUUCUGUCUGGACUUUCCAGAGACCAGUAUUCCCUUUUGCUGCCUCUAAAAGGCCUGUCCCUGCAGACAUGAGAGACAGCAGGUCUCAUGGGGGUGACAAGCUUUUUUUUUUUUUCUUAAAGAAUUUUCAAAAUCAAAUUCCAGAAUGAUUUUACGGAGAUAUCCCAGGAAAAUUAAGGCUUCUCUUAAACACUAAAAAGGCAUGUAAUUGCUUGUUAGCAAAAUGGAUAUGACACAUCUCUGAUACUUUUUUCAUUAUUGGUUGGGCUGAGCAGUCAGAAGACCUGGUCGUCGUCUUGACUUUGGCAAAUGAGCCGGAGCCCCUUGGGCAGGUCACACAACCUGUCCCAGCGAGGGACACCGAGUGGCCCUUCAUGUACAUCCAUGGUGUGCUGGCUUAAAAUGUAAUUAAUCUUGUAAAUAUACUCCUAGUAAUUUAAGAUUUUGUUUUUAAACUGGAAAUAAAAGAUUGUAUAGUGCAUGUUUUUUAAA